CUUUCUGCCGCCAUCUUGGUUCCGCGUUCCCUGCACAAAAUGCCCGGCGAAGCCACAGAAACCGUCCCUGCUACAGAGCAGGAGUUGCCGCAGCCCCAGGCUGAGACAGCUGUGCUACCUAUGUCUUCAGCCUUGAGUGUCACUGCUGCCUUAGGGCAGCCUGGACCUACCCUCCCCCCUCCUUGCUCUCCUGCCCCACAACAGUGCCCUCUCUCAGCUGCUAACCAGGCUUCCCCAUUCCCUUCCCCCUCUACUAUUGCCUCGACCCCUUUAGAAGUUCCUUUUCCCCAGUCAUCCUCUGGAACAGCCCUACCUUUGGGAACUGCCCCUGAAGCCCCAACCUUCCUACCAAACCUAAUAGGGCCUCCCAUCUCCCCAGCUGCCUUAGCUCUAGCCUCUCCCAUGAUAGCUCCAACUCUGAAAGGGACCCCUUCCUCUUCAGCUCCCUUAGCUCUGGUUGCCCUGGCUCCCCACUCAGUUCAGAAGAGUUCUGCUUUUCCACCUAACCUUCUUACUUCACCUCCUUCAGUGGCUGUAGCUGAGUCAGGGUCAGUGAUAACUCUGUCAGCUCCCAUUGCUCCCUCAGAACCAAAGACUAAUCUUAAUAAAGUUCCCUCUGAGGUAGUCCCUAAUCCAAAAGGCACCCCCAGCCCUCCAUGUAUAGUCAGUACUGUUCCUUACCACUGUGUGACUCCCAUGGCCUCUAUUCAAUCUGGAGUGGCCUCCCUUCCUCAGACAACACCCACAACUACCCUAGCCAUCGCUUCCCCUCAAGUCAAAGAUACCACCAUUUCCUCAGUUCUGAUUUCUCCACAAAACCCAGGAAGCCUCAGCCUGAAGGGGCCUGUUAGUCCACCUGCUGCCUUAUCUCUUUCAACUCAGUCUCUUCCUGUGGUGACCUCUUCUCAAAAGACUGCGGGUCCCAACACCCCCCCAGAUUUUCCCAUUUCUCUGGGCUCUCAUCUUGCACCUUUACAUCAGAGUUCUUUUGGUUCUGUCCAACUUUUAGGUCAAACAGGUCCUAGUGCUUUGUCAGACCCUACAGUGAAGACCAUUUCUGUAGAUCAUUCUUCCACAGGGGCCUCUUAUCCUUCUCAGAGAUCUGUAAUUCCUCCCCUUCCUUCCAGAAAUGAGGUAGUUCCUGCUACUGUGGCUGCCUUUCCAGUGGUGGCUCCAUCUGUUGACAAAGGUCCCUCUACCAUCUCUAGCAUAACCUGCAGCCCUUCUGGCUCCUUAAAUGUAGCUACCUCUUUUUCAUUAUCUCCUACAACCUCUCUCAUUCUCAAAAGCUCUCCUAAUGCCACUUAUCAUUAUCCUUUAGUGGCCCAAAUGCCCGUUUCUUCUGUUGGAACCACCCCACUUGUGGUGACUAACCCCUGUACAAUUGCUGCAGCACCUACUACUACCUUUGAGGUAGCUACUUGUGUUUCUCCUCCAAUGUCAUCAGGUCCCAUAAGUAACAUAGAACCAACUUCCCCUGCUGCCUUGGUUAUGGCACCUGUGGCUCCCAAAGAGCCUUCUACUCAAGUAGCAACCACUCUGAGGAUACCAGUCUCUCCUCCUCUGCCAGACCCUGAAGACCUCAAAAAUCUCCCCAGUUCAGUAUUGGUUAAAUUUCCAACACAAAAAGACCUCCAAACUGUACCUGCCUCUCUUGAAGGAGCCCCUUUCUCUCCAGCCCAAGCAGGACUCACCACCAAGAAAGACCCUACUGUAUUACCGUUAGUCCAGGCAGCCCCUAAAAAUUCCCCUUCUUUCCAAAGUACAUCCUCUUCUCCAGAGAUACCUCUUUCUCCUGAAGCCACCCUAGCAAAGAAAAGCCUUGGGGAGCCUCUCCCUAUAGGUAAGCCAGCCAGCAGUAUGACCUCCCCUCUGGGUGUUAACUCCUCGGCCUCUGUAAUCAAGACAGAUUCUUAUGCAGGCCCAGACUCUGCUGGUCCGCUUCUCAAAAGUUCUCUCAUUACCCCAACAGUGGCUGCAUUUCCUUUGGAAAGUGCUGACCCUGCCGGGGUGGCUCCCACAACUGCCAAAGGUACCUCAACUUAUACAACUACAGCCAGCCCUUUUCUAGAAGGAACUGUCUCUUUAGCUCCUAAAAACCACCCAGUUAAGGAAGGUACUCUUACUACUUUACCCUUGGUUCCUACAGCUUCAGAAAAUUGCCCUGUGGCUCCAUCCCCCCAGAAUACCUGUGCUCCUCUGGCUACCUUAGUGCUGGCCCCUGAAAUCCCAAAGUCUGUGCCCUCACCCUCUCUUCCCCCAGCUGGGACUCCUCCAGGUACAAAAAAGGUUGAUGGUAUUUCUCAUACUUCAGCAUUGGCACCUGUUGCUUCCUCUCCCAAAGAGUGCCCAACUGAGGACUCUGGUGCUUCUGCUACUGCAUCUUCCAAAGGAACUCUGACUUACCUAGCUGAUUCCCCAUCUCCUUUAGGGGUUAGUGUGUCUCCUCAGACUAAAAGACCUCCAACCAAGAAGGGUUCUGCUGGCCCUGAUACUCCUAUUGGAAAUCUCUCAUCCCCUGUUUCUCCAGUUGAAGCUUCAUUUCUUCCAGAGAAUAGUCUUUCUUUCCAAGGCUCUAAAGACUCACCAGCCACGACGCAUUCUCCCACUCCUCCAUCCCCCAAAGGGGCCCCUACUCCCUCAGCUGUGACUCCUCUGUCUCCCAAAGGAGUAACACUACCCCCCAAAGAGACCCCCACUCCUUCAGUGGUGAAUCUGCCCUUCCCCAAAGAGGGUCCAGCUACUCCAGCACCCAAACAGGCUCCUGCUCUAUCCAUGACUUCUUCCUCCCCCAAAAAGGCCCGAGCAACUCCAGCCCCUAAAGGAAUCCCAGCUUCCCCAUCCCCCAAAGGGGCCCCCACACCCCCAGCUGCAACUCCUCCCUCCCCUAAAGGAGGCCCAGCUACCCCAUCCCCGAAAUGGGCCCCCACACCCCCAGCUGCAACUCCUCCCUCCCCAAAAGGAGGUCCAGCUACUCCAUCCCCCAAAGGGGCCCCCACACCCCCAGCUGCAACUCCUCCCUCCCCCAAAGGAGGUCCAGCUACUCCAUCCCCCAAAGGGGCCCCCACACCCCCAGCUGUGACUCCUCCCUCCCCCAAAGGAAGUCCAGCAGCUACCCCAUUCCCCAAAGGGGCAUCCACACCCCCAGCUGCAACUCCUCCCUCCCCCAAAGGAAGUCCAGCAGCUACCCCACUCCCCAAAGGGGCCCCCACAACCCCAGCUGCAACUCUUCCCUCCCCAAAAGGAGGUCCAGCUACCCCAUCCCUCAAGGGGGCCCCCACUCCCCCAGCUGCGACUCCUCCCUCCCCAAAAGGAGGCCCAGCUACCCCAUCCCCCAAAGGGGCCCCCAUGCCCCCAGCUGCAACUCCUCCCUCCCCAAAAGGAGGUCUAGCUACCCCACCCCACAAAGGGGCACCCACAACCCCAGCUGCAACUCCUCCCUCCCCAAAAGGAGGUCUAGCUACCCCACCCCCAAAAGGGGCCCCCACAACCCCAGCUGCAACUCCUCCUUCCCCAAAAGGAGGUCUAGCUACCCCACCCCCAAAAGGGGCCCCCACAACCCCAGCUGCAACUCCUCCUUCCCCAAAAGGAGGUCUAGCUACCCCAUCCCCCAAAGGGGCCCCCACAACCCCAGCUGCAACUCCUCCCUCCCCAAAAGGAGGUCUAGCUACCCCAUCCCCCAAAGGGGCCCCCACAACCCCAGCUGCAACUCCUCCCUCCCCAAAAGGAGGUCUGGCUACCCCAUCCCCCAAAGGGGCCCCCACAACCCCAGCUGCAACUCCUCCCUCCCCAAAAGGAGGCCCAGCUACCCCACCCCCCAAAGGGGCCCCCACUCCCCCAGCUGCAACUCCUCCCUCCCUAAAAGGAGGUCUAGCUACCCCACCCCACAAAGGGGCCCCCAAUCCCGCAGUUGUAACUCCUCCCUCUCCAAAAGGAGGCCCAGCUACCUCACCCCCCAAAGGGGCCCCCACUCCUCCAGCUGCAACUCCUCCCUCCCCAAAAGGAAGCCCAGGUACCCCACCCCCCAAAGGGGCCCCCACUCCCCCAGCUGUAACUCCUCCCUCCCCUAAAGGGACCCCUACUCUCCCAGCUACAACUCCCUCCUCUAAAGGAGGCCCAACUACUCCAUCCUCCAAAGAGGGCCCCACUCCCCCAGCUGCAACCCCCUCCCACAAAGGAGGUCCCGCUAUGACUCCUCCCUCCCCCAAAAGAGGACCAGCUAUCCCAUCUCCCAAAGGGGACCCCACUUCCCCAGCAGUGAUUCCUCUCUCCCCCAAAAAGGCUCCAGCAACUCCAGUCACCAGAGAAGGCGCAGCCACCCCAUCCAAAGGAGAUCUCACUCCCCCAGCAGUGACUCCUGUCUCCCUCAAAAAGGCCCCAGCAACUUCAGCCCCCAAAGGAGGCCCAGCUACCCCAUCCUCCAAAGGGGAUCCCACCCUCCCAGCAGUGACUCCUCCUUCCCCCAAGGAGCCCCCAGCCCCCAAACAAGUUGCCACUUCUUCCUCUCCCAAAAAGGCCCCAGCAACUCCAGCCCCCAUGGGGGCCCCCACUCUGCCAGCUGUGAUUCCUUCUUCCCCCAAAGAGGUCCCAGCUACCCCAUCCUCCAGAAGGGACCCCAUUGCCCCAACAGCGACUCUUCUCUCUAAAAAGACCCCAGCAACUCUAGCCCCCAAAGAGGCCCUCAUUCCCCCAGCUAUGACUGUUCCCUCCCCUAAAAAGACCCCAGCAAUUCCAACCCCCAAAGAAGCCCCAGCUACCCCAUCCUCCAAAGAGGCCUCCAGUCCCCCAGCAGUGACUCCUUCCACUUACAAAGGGGCCCCAUCCCCCAAAGAGCUCCUCAUUCCACCAGCUGUGACUUCUCCUUCCCCCAAAGAGGCACCUACUCCUCCAGCUGUGACUCCUCCAUCCCCCGAAAAGGGCCCAGCAACUCCAGCCCCCAAAGGGACUCCCACUUCCCCACCUGUGACUCCUUCCUCCCUCAAAGACUCCCCUACUUCCCCAGCUUCUGUCACAUGUAAAAUGGGGGCCACUGUUCCUCAAGCAUCUAAAGGGCUUCCAGCAAAGAAAGGCCCCACAGCUCUGAAAGAAGUACUUGUUGCCCCAGCUCCAGAAAGCACGCCAAUCAUCACAGCUCCCACUCGGAAAGGUCCACAGACCAAAAAGAGUUCUGCUACUUCACCUCCUAUAUGCCCAGAUCCCUCAGCUAAGAAUGGUUCUAAAGGACCCCUUUCCACAGUGGCUCCAGCCCCUCUACUCCCUGUUCAGAAAGACUCUUCAAAGACAGCAAAAGGCAAAGAUGCUUCUCAUUCCCCAAAGGGCCCCUUGGCUCCUCCUGAGUCUAAGGCGUCCACCCCUCUAACAGCAGCUGCCUUUGAGAAGGUCCUUCCUAAACCUGAAUCAGCAUCUGUCUCUGCAGCACCCUCCCCACCAGUCUCUCUGCCUCUUGCUCCCUCCCCAGUUCCCACUCUGCCUCCUAAACAGCAAUUUCUGCCGUCCUCUCCUGGGCUGGUGUUGGAAUCACCCUCUAAACCCCUUGCCCCUGCUGAUGAGGAUGAGCUGCUGCCUCUGAUUCCCCCGGAACCAAUCUCUGGGGGAGUGCCUUUCCAGUCGGUCCUCGUCAACAUGCCCACCCCUAAAUCUGCUGGAAUCCCUGUCCCAACCCCCUCUGCCAAGCAACCUGUUACGAAGAACAACAAGGGGUCUGGAACAGAAUCUGACAGUGAUGAAUCAGUACCAGAGCUUGAAGAACAGGAUUCCACCCAGGCAACCACACAACAAGCCCAGCUGGCGGCAGCAGCUGAAAUUGAUGAAGAACCAGUCAGUAAAGCAAAACAGAGUCGGAGUGAAAAGAAGGCACGGAAGGCUAUGUCCAAACUGGGUCUUCGGCAGGUUACAGGAGUUACUAGAGUCACUAUCCGGAAAUCUAAGAAUAUCCUCUUUGUCAUCACAAAACCAGAUGUCUACAAGAGCCCUGCUUCAGAUACUUACAUAGUUUUUGGGGAAGCCAAGAUCGAAGAUUUAUCCCAGCAAGCACAACUAGCAGCUGCUGAGAAAUUCAAAGUUCAAGGUGAAGCUGUCUCAAACAUUCAAGAAAACACACAGACUCCAACUGUACAAGAGGAGAGUGAAGAGGAAGAGGUCGAUGAAACAGGUGUAGAAGUUAAGGACAUUGAAUUGGUCAUGUCACAAGCAAAUGUGUCGAGAGCAAAGGCAGUCCGAGCCCUGAAGAACAACAGUAAUGAUAUUGUAAAUGCGAUUAUGGAAUUAACAAUGUAACCAUAUGGAAGCAACUUUUUUUGGUGUCUCAAAGGAGUAACUGCAGCUUGGUUUGAAAUUUGUACUGUUUCUAUCAUAAAUAAAGUUAUGGCUUCUUGUUGGAUGAAUUCA